GCCGGAAGUGCCCCUCGGGGCGGCGCGGCGAGGGACCGGGGCCUCUCCUGCAACCGCCGUUCUGUCGCCACGGAUGGGAAGGAGUCGACCGCGAGAAGAGGACUGGGGGAAGAGGGUCUCAGUGCAGACAGAGUUCUGGAAAAGACUGUUGAUAUCACCCGAGCCGCAGGGCAAGCUGGGAAAGGUAGCUCGGCACAGUCCGGCUGCUGGACUACAAAUCCCAGCAUACUCCUGGAGGAGAGGGCGAGGCGGCAGCCGUGUGGCCUCCACGGCCUCGAAGGAGAUUUGUGGGGUGGCGCGUAUGUGGGGACUCGGCAAUUUAAACACAUCCCGUGAAGAAACUGCCAACAACUAAGUUCCCCCCCCCCCCCCCCCGCUGUAUGUUCCACCCUUCUGGAGCCAUCUUAUUUGCGGCCUGGCCUCCUGGCACAAGGGAUUCUGGAGGUUGUGGUUUCCGAACGGAUCGAGACUGACACCUGAAGGACGCGGCUUAACCGCUUAGCCCCUAGCGGGUCCUGUGGGUUUCCCGACGUCUCCUGGGCUGAAAUGGAAGCGAGAAGUGAUCGGGAACAUUGUGCUGGCAGUUGGAUCCGGCUGCACCGAGCGCCAGCCUUGAAAUAAGUAAAACCGAUGCCCUUCCGCCCCUAACCUCAAAAGCUGCUUUUGCGUCUCGAUGUUAUUGAGAGCCGGCUCUGCGGUCAGCUCUGAGCUAGGCGCUGUGAGAACGCUCAGUAAGACAGUGUCUCGUCUGGAAAUGUACAGGCGAGAUUCAAACCGAGAAACUGCCAAAGGUUGUGUGCAGGGCAGAUCCUAGGAUACCGGAGACCCAGCCCGUUGGCUUGACCUCAAAACUCGGGGGCUUUUCGGCCCAUGCUGUCCCUUAAUUCCUCCUCCUUUGCUGACGCUGUGGGUGCGCAUCAAAGCCUAAACUUCACUAGCUCCCUUGCACACAAGAACACUAACCCUAACCUGACCAGUUAUUUAUUUUUCACUUCAAGAUUCUUCCAUUGAUACUUACGUUUCCCUGAUACCGUCCAAGUGCUGAGGGCGGGGAUGGACUGUGUGAUUUGCAUCUGCCAAAUGCAGAAAAUUUGGAAGUUCACAGCCUCUUAGUUGGAUGCCCCUGUGUCACAGAACACAUUUUGGCUAUGGGGUGUGAUCUGUGUCUGAGGAACAACAAGAAGCUACACGUCAUCCACACAGGAGCCAAAUCUGGAACUCUGGUCUCAGUUCUUCAGGACUAUUUGAGCGAAUAAUCACUCAACACUGGAGUAAAGGAUGUUCUACUAGAAGUCUUAUUCUGACUCCUAAAACCACGCUACCGAAAGUGUUGAUCCACAAACCAGUGCCAGUGCUUGAACUUUGUUACUGGUCCACAGUUAGGAGCUCAGAACACGAUACCCUAAUGGAUGGCACUUUGGCAUGCUGAGUGUUUUGAGCUGAAGGAGACUGGAAGAGCCUCAGAAACAGCAAGCUCCCUCUGACCUUCUCCCUCCCUCCUUUCUCUUUCUCCCAUUUCUCCACAGAAGCAGGUGAUAGAAAAUGGAAUUAUUCUUCCUUAAGGAAGAUAGUAGAAACUAGAACUUCUUACCCCUAAAGCAAGCCAGAAAACCUAGAAAUUAACCUCUGAGCAUCUCCCUUCUCCCCUGAAGACCCUCAUGUGACAGGCAUCCUGCCCUGUACCUGGAGAAAAGAGUACUACUUUUGUAUUUUUAGACAUAAUGCUAUUGCACCCUUGAUAGACUACAGUAUGGUGCAAACACAACUUUUCCCCCUCCUCUACUGUGAAGGGAACAUAACUUUUAUAUGCACUGAGAAACCAAAAAAAUUUGUGUGACUCACCUUGUCGUGAUAUUUGCUUUAUUUCGGCGGUCUGGAACUGAAACUGCAAUAUCUGCGAGGUUUAUCUGUACACGUUUUGCCCCUAUGACAUUUAGGCCAUUUACAAUUUUUGUUAUAAAUAAUGUGGUGAUCUGCUUCUUUGUGUAUAAAGCCUUUGUCUACCUUUCAAAUUAUUAUUUAAUGACAGUUCUAGAAGUAGAAUUACUAUGUAAAGAUUACAAAUAUUUUUACAACUUUUGGUUUAUGUUGCUAAAUUGCUUUUUUUUUUCAGAAGGGCAUUACAAAUCUACACUUUCUUUUCUUUUCUUUUUUUUUUUUUUUUUUUUUUGAGUCAGGGUCUUACUCUGUCACCCAGGCUGGAGUGCAGUGGUGCCAUCAUGACUCACUGCAGCCUCAACCUCCUGGGCUCAGGAGAUACUCCCACCUCAGCCUCCCAAGUAGCUGGAACCACAGGUACACAGCACCACACCGGGCUAAUUUUUUGUGUGUUUUUUGUAGAGACUGGGUUUUGCCAUGUUGCCCAGGCUGGUCUCCAACUCCUGGGCCCAAGCAGUUCUCCUGCCUAGGCCUCCCAAAGUGCUGGGACUACGGGCAUGAGCCACCGUGCCCAGCCCACAAAUUUCUAUUUCUACUUUCAACAGAAAUAUAUUACACCACUGAGUAAGAAUAAUAAGACCUAAUAUUCACGAGGCAUUUAUUUGUUAACCAAGUACUAGUUACUAUAUAUGUAACAGCUCAUCUUUAAAAUCUUGUAUACUGUUGGUGAAAAAGUUGUCUGUUGUUUUAAUUUUAUUUAUUGAUUAAUAGUGAUAUUUAGCUAUAUUUAAAUUUUAAGUUAUUUGUAAGUAUUUGUAGUUGUAAGCUAUUUUUCUAUUAUGAAUUACCAUCCUUAUUGUUUUACAUGAGCUGUUUAUAUAUUGCUGUAUUAACCCUCUGUCAGGUCUGCUUUAGCUAUUUUUUGAGUUGUUUUUAUUGUUUUGGUUUUUUAUUGAUACACAUUACAUAUUUAUUAAGUAUAUGUAAUAUUUUGUGGUUUUUUAAAUUUUAUUUUAUUAAAAAGUUUUUGGUUUUGAGACAAAGUCUCACUCUGUUGCCCAGACUGUGGCACAGUGGCAUGAUCACAGCUCAUUGCAGCCUCAACCUCCUGGGCUCAAGUGAUCCUCCCACCUCAGCCUCCCAAGUAGAUGGACCACAGGCAUGUGCCACCAUGCCUGGCUAAUUUGUUUUUAUUUUUUGUAGAAAUGUCUAUUCAUCUCCUUUGCCCACUUUUCAGUGGGAUUACUUGAGUUGUUUGAGUUCCUUGUAUAAUCUGGAUAUAAUUCCCUUGUGGGAUGAAUAGUUUGCAAACAUUUUCUCCUAUUAAACAGGUUGUCUCUUCACUUCGUUGAUUGUUUCCUUUGCUGUGCAGAAGUUUUUUAGUUUAAUAUAGUCCUAUUUGCUUAUUUUUGUGGGGGUUUUUUUCUGUGCUUUUGAGGUCUUAGCCAUAAACUCUUGCCCUACACCUGUGUCCUAAAGUGUUUUCCCUAUGUUUUCUUCCAGUAGCUUUUAGUUGUAGGUCUUAUAUUUAUGUCUUUGCUCCAUCUUGAGUUUAUUUUUGCAUAUGGUGAUGGACAGGGUUCCAAUUUCAUUUUUCUGUAGAAGCAUAUCCAAUUUUCUAAGCACCAAUUAUUGAAGAGGGUGUCCUUUUCUCAAUGUCUGUUAUUGGCACCUUUGUAGACAAUCAGUUGGCUGGAAAUAAGUGGAUUUACUUCCGGAUUCUGUGUUCUGUGGUCUAUGUGUCUGUUUUUAUACCAAUACCACCCUACUUUGAUUGCUAUGCUAUAACCUUGUAAUAUAUUUUGAAGUCAGGUAGUGUGAUGCCUCUUGCUUUGUUCUUUUUACUCAGGAUUGCUUUGGCUCUUCAAGCUCUUUUUUGAUUCUACAUGAAUUUUAGGAUUUUUUCCCCUAUUUCUGUAAAAAAUGACAUUGGUCUUUUCAUAGGAGUUGCAUUGAAUCUGAUUAUUGCUUUGGGUAGUUUGGUCAUUUUAAGAGCGUUAAUUCUUCUGAUCUAUGAACAAAAUAUGUCUUUUCAUUUGUUUGUGUCCUCUUCAAUUUCUUUCAUCAGCAUUUUGUAGUUUCCCUUAUAGAAGUCUUUCACUUCCUUGGUUAAAUUUAUUCUUAGUCAUUUCUCUUUUGUAGCUACUGUAAAUGGGAUUACCUUCUUGAUUUCUUUCUCAGCUAGUUCAUUAUUGGUGUAUAGAAAUGCUACUGAUUUUUGUACAUUGAUUUUGUAUCCUGCAAAUUUAAUGAAUUCAUUUAUCAGUUCUAAAAGUUUUUGGGUGCACCCUUUAGGUUUUUCUAGAUAUAAGAUCAUGUCAUCUGCAAAGGGGAACAAUUUGACUUCCUCUUUUCCAAUCUGGAUGCCUUUUAUUUCUUCCUCUUGCCUGAUUGCUCUGGCUAGGACUUUCAAUCCUGUGUUGAAUAGGAGUGGUGCAAGUGGGCAUCCUUGUCUUGUUCCAGUUCUUAGGGGAAAGGCUUUCAUCUUUUCCCCAUUCAGUAUGAUGUUAGCUGUGGGUUUGUCCUAUAUGGCCUUUAGUAUGUUGAGGUAUGUUCCUUCUAUGCCUAGUUUGUUGGGAAUUCUUACCAUGAAGGUAUGUUGAAUUUUAUCAAAUGCUUUUUCUGGGUCAAUUGAGAUGAUCAUAUAGUUUUUGUCCUUCAUUCUGUUGAUGUAAUGUAUCACAUUUAUUGAUUGGCGUAUGUUGAACCAUCCUUACAUCCCUGAGAUAAAUCUCUCUUAAUAAUGGUGUAUUACCUUUUUGAUGUGCUGUUGGAUUCAGUUUGCUAGUAUUUCAUUGAGGAUUUUUGCAUCUGUGUUCAUCGGGGAUAAUGACCUUAGUUUUCUUUUUUUGUUGUUUGGUCCUUGUCUUAGUUUGGUAUAAGGAUAAUGCUGGCCUCAUAGAAUGAGUUAGGAAGAAUUCUCUCCUCUUCACUUUUUUGGAAUAGUUUGAGAAGAAUUGGUGUUAGUUCUUUGUAAGUUUGGUAGAAUUCAGCAGUGAAGCCAUCUGGUCCUGGACUUUUCUUUGUUGAGAGACUUUUUAUUACUGAUUUAAUUUCAUUACUCAUUAUUGGUCUGUUCAGGUUUCCAUAUUUUUCUUAUUCAAUCUUGGUAGGCUGUAUGUGUCCAAUAAUUUGUUCAUUUCCUCUAGGUUUUCCAGUUUGUUAGUGUAUAGUUGUUCAUAACAGUCUCUGAUGAUUUUUUGUAUUUCUGUGGCAUCAGUUACAAUGUCUCCUUUUUCAUUUCUGAUUUUUUUUUUUUUUUUGAAACAAGGUCUCACUCUGUUGCCCAGGCUGGAGUGCCGUGGUGCAAUCUCAGCUCACUGCAAUAUCCACCUCCUAGAUUCAAGCAAUUCUCCUGCCUCAGCCUCCUGAGUAGCUGGGAUUACAGGCACGUGCCACCAUAUCCAGCUAAUUUUGGUAUUUUUAGUAGAAAUGGGGUUUCACCAUGUUGGUCCACCUGCCUGGGCCUUCCAAAGUGCUGGGAUUACAGGCAUGAGCCUCUGUGCCCGGCCCAUUUCUGAUUUUAUUUAUUUGUGUCUUCUCUCCUUUUUCUUGGUUAGUCUAGCUAGCGAUUUAUCAAUUUUGCUUACUUUUUCAAAAAGACAACUUUUCAUUUCAUUGAUCCUUUGUAUUGUUUUUUAAGUCUGUAUUUCAUUUAAUUCUGCUCUGAUCUUUAUUAUUAAUUUUAUUCUACUAAUUUGGGGUUUGGAUUGUUCUUGCUUUUUUUUUUCCUUUGAGUCAGGGUCUUGCUCUGUUGCCCAGGCUGGAGUACAAUGGCUCUAUGAUGGCUUAUUCCAGCCUUGACCCUCUGGGCUCAAGUGAACCUCCCACUUUAGCAUCCUAAGUGGCUGGGACCACAAUUGUGCACCACUGUGUCUGGCUAAACUUUUUUAAUGUUUUGUAGAGACAGGGUCUCCCUAUGUUGCCUAAGUAUGUUGCCUAAGCUGGUCUCAAACUCCUGGGCUCAAGCCAUCCUCCUGAUUCAGCCUCCCAAAGUGCUGGGACUACAGGAGUGAGCCACCAUGCCUGGCCCGUUCUUGCUUUUCCAGUUCCUUGAAGGCAUCUUUAGAUCAUUUAUUUGAAAUCUUCCUACUUUUUUGAUGUAGGUGUUUAUUGAUAUAAACUCCCCUCUUAGCACUGCUUUUGCUGUAUCCCAUAGGUUUUCGUACGUUCUAUGUCAAUUUCCAUUUGUUUCAAUAAAUUUUUUUUAAAUUUUCUUUAAGAUAUUUUACGUUUCUUCUAUGUUGUGGAAUCUAUUGAGUUUUACUUUAUGAUUCAUCCUUGCUUUUUAAAACAUUUAAUUUUAUUUAAUGGUUCAGUAAUAAUAAAGAUACCCUUUUACAUGUUUACAGUACCUCAUUGUUUACAUACACUAUUUCAAGCUUUUGGAAUAGGGACAACUAAAACAGAUUCUUGUGUAAAUGAGUUUCUUUAUAUAACUUCACAUUCUUUAUGUAAUGGUUCUUUUGAAGCUUAACAAGUUCUUUCUCAACAACUGUAUUUUUUUAAUGUGGAAUUGACUAAGUAUAUGAAAAUAUGAAAUAAACAAAAUAAAAUGGAAAACUAUGAGGUCCUUAGAAGUCACAUUACAUCCCUAUAUUUGGUGACAUUUAAAGAGAUGAAUGACAUCAUUGAGAAGUAAGGAGAAAUACAGUGCAGCAAAUCAAGAACAUGCCACUCAUGUAAGAGUGAACAUCUAUCUCCAGGCAUGAGAAAGGUCUAGAGAGUUCUUAACAAAAUGCUGUCAGUGUUUAUUUCUCAGUCUUGAGACGUCAGAUGAUUUUUAUGAUCUUCUUUGUGCUUUUCUAAUUUGUUUAAUAUUUUACAGUAAGCAUGUAUCAUUUUUACUAAAAUAUCCACGUUAUUGUUUAAAACAGGAACAAAAUUUUUCUACAUGCACAAGGAUAAUAGUAUUUGUCUAUAUUUUUUUCUGGUCUUUUAAUUAAGUGUUUAUACACACAGAGAGACAGGAAUAAAGUUUUCCUUAGCAUUUAAAUAAUUUCCAAGAAGUAUAUACAUUCCUACAUAUGGGUUAAAUAAACACACAUAUGUCAAUAAACAUAUAUUCUAACAAACUCAGGCCUGCUAAAUGCGGCUAAAAGUUCCCAGUGAAAAGAACUCUUAGGUGAGCUAUAUUUUCUAAUCUGCAGACCCUCCUACUGCAUAACUCUGGAUGAUGUCAUACAAACCUCUUCCUGCAUCUGGGACUCUUUCCAGCUGCUACAUGUGGGAGCUUCCCGUUUUUGUUCUAAUUGAGUGAUGUUUACUGGAAAUGGAGUCUGCUAAUAAGAUCUCAGUUCAGAUAGCUUUGUGGGGACAGGAAGAAUGAUUGUGAGAUGAAUUUGGCCAAAAACCUUUACUUUCUCCCUUGUCAUUAUCUUGUUUUGAUAGGUUGGCUUAGUUUUGUUUUGAAAUUACCUCUUCUGAGAAACCAAAGAGGAACGAUAUGCGCUGUCUUCUUCUUCCUCCUCCUCCUCCUCCUUUUCCUCUUCCUACCAAGACUCCCAACUCAGACUGUUUUUCAGUCUGUCCCUCCAUACAUACCUGCACACUCACACAUCUACUAGAGAGUAUAUGGAGACAGCCAAGAGCCCUUAGAAAGAUAGCUGGGUAAUGUACUACUCUGUUCUCUUGAAUUUGGAUGGAACUUAUGACAACACUUAGAUGUGAACAAAUAAGGCAAGAGAAUUUGUCCCAGAUUGCACAGCUGGUUAUGGCAGAACAAAGCGGUGGUGAACCUAGAUUUCAUAUCUCCUAGCUCAGGGCCUCUGGAUUAAAACCCAUAAACAUUGUUCACAUUUUUUUGGAACUAUGCAUAAGGGCAACUUAGAGAGUUCCAGGUAAGAGAAUGCAGCAUAACAAGAGUUGAUUGUUUUAAGUUGUGUUAUGUUAAAGAUCAGCUAAGUAAAAUUAAAGAGAAAAGCUGCUAAAUAUACUGAAUUAUUUCAUUUUUGUGGAUCUCCUUGAUUGUGAUUUGCGAGCUCAGAAGUAUUAACAGUUUUUCUCAAAAAUUUUAAGAUGAAAAAUUCUCAAGUCCAAUUAAUUGAAAAGCUUAAGACUACUCUAUACCAUGCUUCACUUUAGAAAGUAGGGAGCUUGUUGCAAAUUCAAACAAGGAUGUGGUGUCACAACUCAUGAAAGGAAUCUCUUAUCAAAUAUCUAUCCUACCAUCAAAUUGCCAUUACAUCUGCCCGAAUGUACAUGGGACACAGUUGCGUCAGAAAGGCUAAAGCUCCAAAUAAGUUCACAUUAUUCUGAAACUAUCAGAUUAUGUGAUGGAUAUAAUUUGGGUGUUACAGUCUUUGUAGUAAAGUUUGAGGAAUGACACCAGGUAUGGUCGAGUGCAGUGGCUCAUGCCUAUAAGAUGAGCCUAGGCAACAUGGUGAGAUCCCAUCUCUACAAAAAAUACAAAAAUUAUCCAGGCAUGGUGGGGUGGUGUGCACCUGUAGUCCCAGCUACUCAGGAGGUUCCAGUGGGAGGAUUACUUGAAACCAGGAGGUUGAGACUGUAGUGAGCCAUGUUUGUGCCACUGUACUCCAGCCUGGGCAACAGAGCAAGACUGUCUCAAAAAAAAAAAAAAAAGAAAGAAAGAGAAAAAAAAACCCCAUCAGGUAAAAUGUAGGGCCACUGUCAAUGGGGGACAUAGAGAAAACAGAGAUCUUCAAUUCUCUUCUGCUUCUAACUUUCGGGACAAGGACAUUUUUUCUCCACAUGUUAUCAGUAAGGUGAGGAGAAAUAGAGAAAGAGCAUAAACUUUGGUAAGCGAAGAUAGAAGCCCAAGAUGGAAUAAUAGAGUGAGAAAGAGCCCAAAGCUGCUCCAAGUGAUUUCAAGUCCCCAGUUUUGAAGAAUGAUGUCUUUGGGUCUUGAGAAAACAUUGUUGUGGGAUCACCAACAAUCGUCAGGGAUAUUUGGGGCAUCAUAGAGAAUAGGAGAGAUUCCAGAAGACUGGUAACAGUGGAGUAUUCUGAUUUUCAGAAAGAGAAAGCAGAGCCAGAAAAAAAUGUAGAUAAUGGUCUGUAACCUCAAUCUCAGGCCAGAGUCUAGAAGGGGGGAUUAUUAGAGGAACAGUUUCAGGCACUAGAUAAAAAAGGAAUGAUUAAGAUCCAGAUGAGUUCACUAAAAACAAGUCAGGGCUAAUUUAUCUCUUGGCUUUGACAGAGUUACCAGCCCAGUACCUCAGGGAAUGCCCAUACAUAUAGAAUAUUUUGUUAUCAGUUAGACAUUUAAUAAAGUUUUUUUUUCAUGAUAUUCUUUUGGACAAGACAGAGAGAUAUAAACUGAAUUGUGGCACACUGAAUGAAUUAGAAACCAGUCAAUUGUACGCACAGGUGCUGGCUAACAAACUGUAAAGAAGCAUGCAGUGGACACACCCAGAUCCCUUUAUUCCAGAACACAUAACUUAAAGUCACACUUUCCUGAGAUCAGAGCAGAGGAUGGCAGAGAACCAAAGUCACGAGUGUGUGAAACAACGGAGAGGAGCGGCGCUGUGCAGCCUGGAGCUCAAGACACUUGCAUGAGCGCCUAGGGGAGACAACCAUCUCAGUAAUGAUCCUAAUUGGAUCCAACUGGGGAACUCCAGAAAGUUUCAGUAACAAAUUUGCAAUGGUUCUGGGCCUUUUAAUAUGGAUUCACAAAAGAUAAUGAGGUUAUCCUGUCAUUUCUACCCUAUGGAUGAGGAAAGUGACAUUCAGACAGGCCAUGGGAUCUACCCACUCCCUCGUAAAGAACUGGAGGACCAACAUUAGCAACAGGACCUCCCAUUUGGCAUUUUGUUUUCAGAUGUGCCUAGAAGAAGGAGAUUACAGCUUCUUGGACUGUUGAAGCCUGGGUUCUUCUUGAGUUGUGAAGAUAUCACCUAAAUCCUAUCCACAUUUUGUGCACCAGGUUUGUGGACGCCUACCACCAUUCAUUCAUUGCAGUGGCUCAGAGAAGAUGAAAACAGGACUCUUUGGGGCCAAUGAAGAUCCCCAACAGAGCUCAGAUGACCAGAGUGGACUGGCUUCUACCCUAAAUACAUACAACAAUACUUCCCACUCUGACCUUGCUCACUUUAUACAACACCACACAACUAGAGAGUGGCAGAGCUGCUGUGGGAACCCAAAUGCCAUCUGACUCCAAAGCCUUACUCUCAACCACCACCCUGCUGCCUCCUAUUCUUUCCUGAAAUCUUCAGUAUAGUCAUUAUUAUGAAGUAAAAAAAAAAAGAAAAUGAAAGGAUGGAAGGAAGGUAGAGGGAGCCCCUCUAUCUCCAUUCUUUGUUUCCAUGAAGAACCUCUACUCCAUUUUCAGGGGAGUGCUAUUGGUGUAACACACUUUCUGGCCCUCUCCCUCCCAUUCUUGUCACUCAUUCUCCCCAAGGAAGAAGCGAUAUGUGGAUGAUAAGAUUGGAAGAAGCCACUCUUAUGUUCGGUGGUGUGCUGGUAAAUGUUUAGCAGCUGGCUCUGGGGCAGAGAGAAAGCCCUGAAUUGUAGUAUGUGCCAAUCUCCAUGGUGUAAAAACACUUCUACCAUAGCUGCUUCCAAGUAUGUAAAUUGUACACCUCAAUAAAGCCAAUUUAAAAAGUAAAGUCAAUCAGUUUGUAAAACUCUUGAGACUUUAACAUUCAGUCCAGCAAGCUGUUACCUGCCGGAUCCAGCAACACACAACCCGUAACAUAACGAGUUGGGUCUCAGCUCCCCGCUCUUCACAGACUCCAGAGUUCUCUCCCCUUUGUGGGGUUCCUCAUCCAUCCUUCCAUUGCUUCUGCUGCUGCCCUGAAGGCAUCACCGCUCUCCCGUCUCCUCUUGGGGCACCUAACUCUCUUAACAGUUUAGGACUUUGAGGAGUUUUGCCUUUCACAAAAAGAAAGAAUGGGGGAAAAACGGUUAUGCCUCAGCAGCUUUCGCUGUCUACCCUGCAGCACAAAUUCCACUUGAUGGAGGAACACAAAGGUCGGACUCCCUGCCGUGAAGAGGAGAAAGGGAAAUUCGAAUAUGGAAGGAGCUCUACUCUCCCUUGCUCUGUCCUCCGCAAGAGAAUGGGGCAGAACAUUCUUUAGUCUACACCUCUGUCCCACAUGAGUUGCCAAAGACCACAGUGCCUGGUGGGUGACAUCUCUCCAGGCUUUUGAAGACAUCUGAGCCUGGAUUUUGAGCACAUUCCUGACCUCCCUACUGGGAGGCUCUUCUCCUUCAAGGUCUGCCUUCUGACAAGCCCUAGCUCUUUCCCACCUCCAGUGGCUGGGUGGGCCGGGGGGUGGGGUAAGGGUGGAGAUGUGGGCACAUUCUGGGAGCCCCACCAGAACCCCAUGGAGUGGAGAAGUGACCUUCUAAGGAGGGGAGCGUACAGUUUCCGGAAGGGAGGAAGGAUGCGGUGAGGACCAAAUGCAUCCAUGCAGGAUUUCAAAUAUAAACGACUCUAUAGAAUACAAGCACCUACUCCUGGCAACCGAAGCCGAAGGAAGCCUAAGAAUAUAAGAGACGGGGCUUCGGCGAGGGCACGUGACCGAAAACUCACAUAACACUCCACCUGCCCCAGUCCAGCCAGCCUGCUGUCCACAGUGUGCCCAUCAGUGUAUCAAACCUCAGUGCUUUAUUUCCUGGGAUCCUGGCCGAGCUCCCAUUAACCUCCUGUGUUGUCCCCACAGCUCCUAUACAUGGGAGAGGGCCUGCGUUGGGCCAGAUCCCAGAGCUGGGGCCUAAUUUGUGAUGGGAUGCCCUGGGAGGCAAGCGUGCUUCAGCAUGUACCCAAUCAAUAGCCAGACACCCAGGUCCGGAGGUGCCUGAGUCGGUCAGCAGGACGUUGGGCAGGUCUAGGUUCAGAACCUCUGCAGUUUUUCCCUUGGCUUCCCCGGGGCUUGUCCACAACGCCCCCUGCUGCCCAUUCUUGGUUAACCUUGUGUCUUGUGGAUACCUCAUCAGAUCUGUUCAUGAAGCCUAACGCAAGGUCCUCCCUCCAGGGUGACACAGUGAAGUCAAGUAACAGAUGUGGAGAUGCUUUGGAGAGCUUGAAACAGAAGACUACAUAAUAACAAUGGGCCAGUAUCAUAAAGCCAAGAUUGAAGAAGACAGAACUGAAUAUCUCCCUCAUCUGCAAAACUUGCCUUAUCUUUCAGUAUCAUCCUGUUUCAGUGGACAGAAAUCAAUCCAUCAUAUAUUUGAGCCCUGCUCUUAUAACCAAGUUAAAUUUUGCCUAAAAUAAGGCCCUGCCUCAAGCAAAUCAUGGUCCCCUCAGUGAUUCCUGUGUGCACCCAGGGUUGAGAACUACUGCAUAAGAGGUCCUAGAAGAUAUCUGGUAUGGCCAGAGUACAGAGGGACCGGAGAAGAACUUCUGCUUGGGUGGCUGAACUCUGAUCUUGACCUAGAGUCAUGGCCAUGGCAACCAAAGGAGGUACUGUCAAAGCUGCUUCAGGAUUCAAUGCCAUGGAAGAUGCCCAGACCCUGAGGAAGGCCAUGAAAGGGCUCGGCACCGAUGAAGACGCCAUUAUUAGCGUCCUUGCCUACCGCAACACCGCCCAGCGCCAGGAGAUCAGGACAGCCUACAAGAGCACCAUCGGCAGGGACUUGAUAGACGACCUGAAGUCAGAACUGAGUGGCAACUUCGAGCAGGUGAUUGUGGGGAUGAUGACGCCCACGGUGCUGUAUGACGUGCAAGAGCUGCGAAGGGCCAUGAAGGGAGCCGGCACUGAUGAGGGCUGCCUAAUUGAGAUCCUGGCCUCCCGGACCCCUGAGGAGAUCCGGCGCAUAAGCCAAACCUACCAGCAGCAAUAUGGACGGAGCCUUGAAGAUGACAUUCGCUCUGACACAUCGUUCAUGUUCCAGCGAGUGCUGGUGUCUCUGUCAGCUGGUGGGAGGGAUGAAGGAAAUUAUCUGGACGAUGCUCUCGUGAGACAGGAUGCCCAGGACCUGUAUGAGGCUGGAGAGAAGAAAUGGGGGACAGAUGAGGUGAAAUUUCUAACUGUUCUCUGUUCCCGGAACCGAAAUCACCUGUUGCAUGUGUUUGAUGAAUACAAAAGGAUAUCACAGAAGGAUAUUGAACAGAGUAUUAAAUCUGAAACAUCUGGUAGCUUUGAAGAUGCUCUGCUGGCUAUAGUAAAGUGCAUGAGGAACAAAUCUGCAUAUUUUGCUGAAAAGCUCUAUAAAUCGAUGAAGGGCUUGGGCACCGAUGAUAACACCCUCAUCAGAGUGAUGGUUUCUCGAGCAGAAAUUGACAUGUUGGAUAUCCGGGCACACUUCAAGAGACUCUAUGGAAAGUCUCUGUACUCGUUCAUCAAGGGUGACACAUCUGGAGACUACAGGAAAGUACUGCUUGUUCUCUGUGGAGGAGAUGAUUAAAAUAAAAAUCCCAGAAGGACAGGAGGAUUCUCAACACUUUGAAUUUUUUUAACUUCAUUUUUCUACACUGCUAUUAUCAUUAUCUCAGAAUGCUUAUUUCCAAUUAAAACGCCUACAGCUGCCUCCUAGAAUAUAGACUGUCUGUAUUAUUAUUCACCUAUAAUUAGUCAUUAUGAUGCUUUAAAGCUGUACUUGCAUUUCAAAGCUUAUAAGAUAUAAAUGGAGAUUUUAAAGUAGAAAUAAAUAUGUAUUCCAUGUUUUUAAAAGAUUACUUUCUACUUUGUGUUUCACAGACAUUGAAUAUAUUAAAUUAUUCCAUAUUUUCUUUUCAGUGAAAAAUUUUUUAAAUGGAAGACUGUUCUAAAAUCACUUUUUUCCCUAAUCCAAUUUUUAGAGUGGCUAGUAGUUUCUUCAUUUGAAAUUGUAAGCAUCCGGUCAGUAAGAAUGCCCAUCCAGUUUUCUAUAUUUCAUAGUCAAAGCCUUGAAAGCAUCUACAAAUCUCUUUUUUUAGGUUUUGUCCAUAGCAUCAGUUGAUCCUUACUAAGUUUUUCAUGGGAGACUUCCUUCAUCACAUCUUAUGUUGAAAUCACUUUCUGUAGUCAAAGUAUACCAAAACCAAUUUAUCUGAACUAAAUUCUAAAGUAUGGUUAUACAAACCAUAUACAUCUGGUUACCAAACAUAAAUGCUGAACAUUCCAUAUUAUUAUAGUUAAUGUCUUAAUCCAGCUUGCAAGUGAAUGGAAAAAAAAAUAAGCUUCAAACUAGGUAUUCUGGGAAUGAUGUAAUGCUCUGAAUUUAGUAUGAUAUAAAGAAAACUUUUUUGUGCUAAAAAUACUUUUUAAAAUCAAUUUUGUUGAUUGUAGUAAUUUCUAUUUGCACUGUGCCUUUCAACUCCAGAAACAUUCUGAAGAUGUACUUGGAUUUAAUUAAAAAGUUCACUUUGUAAGAACGUGGAAAAAUAAUUUUAAUUUAAAAAUGGUGUUUUUAGGCCGGGGGCGGGGGCUCACGCCAGUAAUCCCAACACUUUGGGAGGCCAAGGCGGGUGGAUCACCUAAGGUCAGGAGUUCAAGACUAGCCUGGCCAACAUGGAGAAACUGCAUCUCUACUAAAAAUAUAAAAAUUAGCCGGGUGUGGUGGCUGGUGCCUGUAAUCCCAGCCACUCGGAGGCUGAGUCAGGGAGAACUGCUUGAACCCAGGAGGCAGGAGGCAAAGGUUGCAGUGAGCCGAGAUCACGCCAGCCUGGGCGACAGAGCGAGAAUCCAUCUAAAAAAAAAAAAAAAAAAAGUGUCUUUAAAGUGAGGUAUAGUCUUUCUCUGAUCCACUUUUCACCUUCUGAGGUUUUUCAUCUUGGCCCCUGAAAGGAGCUAUUUUUGAAGGACUUGUGUUACUCAGUUUCUACAGGAAUUACAAGAUAAGAAAAAAAAAAUCAUAUUUAGUCUUAUGCGUGCCUACUGGCUAAUGUUCACAUAUGCCAAACACUACUCAAUAACAUAAAAUAAUGUAUGAACUUAUUCUCUGGAAAUGAGUGAUGCCCUCUGCUCUAAGUAGACCAUUUAUAUUAAAUAUCAUAAAUGUAUAAAGGACAUUCAUAUUCUUA